CAAGAUCAUACCAUUGCACUCCAGCCCAGGUGACACAGCAAGACCCUCUCUCAAAAAUAAAUAAAAUUGUGGCUGCAAAACAAGAGAGGAGGGAGCAGGGACUAUAACCAGCCUAGGGCUUUUCUCUGGAUCCUGCUGCCACCUCUUCUUAACUCCCAUUCUGGAGCCCACCCAUCUGCCUUACACCCACCAGCUCAUGGCAUCAUCUUUCUCUAUAUCCCUUUCCCAGUGGCUUCCUCCCUAUCCCAGUCCCCUGAUGCAAAUCCUGAUGUCAUCUGCCCCAGCCACCCAUCUCUACCUCAACCCUCACUUCUCUGGUGAGAACUCUUGUGGAUCCAGGGAGUGUCAAAUCCCAGCCUGAACCAAACCUCAACUGAGAUUAUAUUAUCCUAUAAUAUACCUUCUCCCCUCCCCUCCCCUCCCACCAUUGGAAUCACCCUCAGGAGAGCAGCUCCACUCUUCUCAUCCAGAAGGGGCCCAUGGCCCUAAGAAGGGCCAUAGAUUGCCAUAGGUUGGCUUUUGGCAUCCCCCAGCUCUCCUUCGACAUCCCUGUGUGGCUCAUCCCACCCUUACCCUGCUUCUUGUCCUCCCCACAGUCCUGUGGCCCAAGCUUUUCAAGUUGGUGAAAGAGACAGUUGUGAUCUGACAAGGGCUAGACAGGUGCUUCACCCUCUGUCACCAAAUACCCUCAUUAUCCAGCCCAAAACACCUCCAUUCAUUCCUUUCUAUUCUGGCACAUAUUCGUUAAUUCAUUCCAUCAUUCACCUAACACCCUUGAAGCAGAGCCAAUCACCUCUACCAACAUCUUCCUAGAGACAAAUAGAUUAACUGGGGUGGGGUAAACUUUGAGAGCUCCAAAAGGAAAGCUCCAGAGGACGGGGGUUCUGCAGGGGUCCAGGCCUCUCAGGGACCACAGAGCAGACCUGCAGCAGAGGCAGAAUUAGAGCCCAUGGCUCUGGAGUCAACCAGGGCCAGGCAGAGGGCACCAGCUCUUGGCUGCUGAAAGUAGAGCUCUUCAAAAGUCAUCCACUCAGUCAGCAUCUACUGAGUGCCAGGCAGUGUCGUCACCUCUACAGCCGUCAGGGGAGAGAACAGCAGCCUAGAGAAAGGGAGUCUGAGCCCCCAUCCCACGGGCUCGAAGCCCAGAGUAGAGGCCAGCACUAGUGCCUCUGACCCAGAGGACGAAGCUCUAAGGAGGUCACAGAUGAGGAAGGGUCCAGUGCUCGGCGCAGACUCCGUGCGGAGCCCCUAGGCCCCGCAGCUCGCCCCUCCCUCUCCCCUACUCCCCUCCUCUCCCCCUCCCGUCUCUCCCCCGCCUCUUCGCUCUCGCUCGGCUCCCUCUCUAGCUGACCUUCCCUUUCCCUCACGCCUCCCCACGCCCGGCCCCUGGCCCCAGCACCCUGUCCGCUGCCGCCUCAGAGCCGGGAAAAGCAGCCGGAGCCCCCGCCGCCCCUGCCGCAGCGCGGGCGGUCAGCGCGCAGCCCGGCACCCGCAGCCUGCAGCCUGCAGCCCGCAGCCCGCAGCCCGGAGCCAGAUCGCGGGCUCAGACCGAACCCGACUCGACCGCCGCCCCCAGCCAGGCGCCAUGCUGCCGCUUCUGCUGGGCCUGCUGGGCCCAGCGGCCUGCUGGGCCCUGGGCCCGACCCCCGGCCCGGGAUCCUCUGAGCUGCGCUCGGCCUUCUCGGCGGCACGCACCACCCCCCUGGAGGGCACGUCGGAGAUGGCGGUGACCUUCGACAAGGUGUACGUGAACAUCGGGGGCGACUUCGAUGUGGCCACCGGCCAGUUUCGCUGCCGCGUGCCCGGCGCCUACUUCUUCUCCUUCACGGCUGGCAAGGCCCCGCACAAGAGCCUGUCGGUGAUGCUGGUGCGAAACCGCGACGAGGUGCAGGCGCUGGCCUUCGACGAGCAGCGGCGGCCAGGCGCGCGGCGCGCAGCCAGCCAGAGCGCCAUGCUGCAGCUCGACUACGGCGACACAGUGUGGCUGCGGCUGCAUGGCGCCCCGCAGUACGCGCUAGGCGCGCCCGGCGCCACCUUCAGCGGCUACCUAGUCUACGCCGACGCCGACGCUGACGCGCCUGCGCGCGGGCCGCCCGCGCCCCCCGAGCCGCGCUCGGCCUUCUCGGCGGCGCGCACGCGCAGCUUGGUGGGCUCGGACGCUGGCCCCGGGCCGCGGCACCAACCACUCGCCUUCGACACCGAGUUCGUCAACAUUGGCGGCGACUUCGACGCGGCGGCCGGCGUGUUCCGCUGCCGUCUGCCCGGCGCCUACUUCUUCUCCUUCACGCUGGGCAAGCUGCCGCGUAAGACGCUGUCGGUUAAGCUGAUGAAGAACCGCGACGAGGUGCAGGCCAUGAUUUACGACGACGGCGCGUCGCGGCGCCGCGAGAUGCAGAGCCAGAGCGUGAUGCUGGCCCUGCGGCGCGGCGACGCCGUCUGGCUGCUCAGCCACGACCACGACGGCUACGGCGCCUACAGCAACCACGGCAAGUACAUCACCUUCUCCGGCUUCCUGGUGUACCCCGACCUCGCCCCCGCCGCCCCGCCGGGCCUCGGGGCCUCGGAGCUACUGUGAGCCCCGGGCCAGAGAAGAGCCCGGGAGGGCCAGGGGCGUGCAUGCCAGGCCGGGCCGGAGGCUCGAAAGUCCCGCGCGAGCGCCACGGCCUCCGGGCGCGCCUGGACUCUGCCAAUAAAGCGGAAAGCGGGCACGCGCAGCGCCCGGCAGCCCA